UGCUCCUCUACCUGCUCUACUCUCAAUCCGCCAGAAUCAUGGGCUGCUGUGGCUGUUCUGGAGGCUGUGGCUCUGGCUGUGGGGGCUGUGGCUCCGGCAGUGGGGGCUGUGGCUCUGGCUGUGGGGGCUGUGGCUCCAGCUGCUGUGUGCCCAUUUGCUGCUGCAAGCCUGUGUGCUGCUGUGUGCCAGCCUGUUCCUGCUCCAGCUGUGGCUCCUGUGGGGGCUCCAAAGGGGGCUGUGGCUCUUGUGGGAGCUCCAAGGGUGGGUGUGGUUCUUGUGGCUGCUCCCAGUCCAACUGCUGUAAGCCCUGCUGCUCCUCCUCAGGCUGUGGGUCAUUCUGCUGCCAGUCCAGCUGCUCCAAACCCUGCUGCUGCCAAUCCAGCUGCUGCCAGUCCAGCUGCUGCAAGCCCUGCUGCUGCCAAUCCAGCUGCUGCCAGUCUAGCUGCUUCAAGCCCUGCUGCUGCCAGUCCAGCUGCUGUGUCCCCGUGUGCUGCCAGUGUAAGAUCUGAGGCUCUGGACCCAGACCUUCAGGUUUCUCCUCUUUGGUGAAAGCAUUUCUUAUGGUUUCUCUGAAUCAGUUCAUCCCACACAUCAUCCUGAGGCACCUGCACCUGCUCUAGCUCAUCAUCCAUGCAUGCACCUCUUUCCAUGGCUCGGCUCUCCUCUAGGCCCUGCCUUCAGCUUCCUCACUCCGGAAACAUGUGUUUCCUUGAUGCAGGAGGUGUUCUUCCCUGGACGCCAUGGUGUUCCCUGCACUUGGGUGUGGACCAUCUUCUUCUUCUCCCUGGGCUGACUGAGAUGCUAGGUCUGACCCCACAAGGCCAGGCCGACAUUCCUGAGUGAUCACUAAGAACCAGUUUCUCAACCACCACUGGGAUUCUGGGUCCUCCUGGGCUGCUGCCUGUUCUCCUGUGACCCACCUGUGAGCAAGAAGGUCUCCUUCCUUCCUGUUGUCUCCAUCUAUUUAAAAAAAAAAUGAAUGAAUUUCCUUGCAAUAAAGCCUCUCAUGUCUGUAAACCAA